CUGUCUGUGACUCCAUCAAAGUUUCCUCAUGUUCUCUGGGCCUCAGUUUCCACCUCUGGGUGGUCGGUUUCUGGGUCUGCAUGGCUCAGUAGAGGAUGAAGUCCAACCCCCCACGCUCCUCCCUAGAGGCCUGCAAAGCUGCAGGCCAGGGUGAGAAGAGCUGCCCUGUCUGCCAGGCCUGUGGAGAGGUCUCAGGUCCAAGGUCUGGCUCAGGGUCUGAGUCAAGGCCUGCACCAAAGCCUGGUGCCAUUCCAGGGCCUGGACUGGGGCCCAAAGCUAUUCCAGGACCUCAGGCGGGUUCUGGUACUGUUCCGAGGCCUGGUGCUAUUUCAGGGACUGGACCAGGUCUAGGGCCUGGGCCAGGAGCUGGGUCUGUACCUGGGCCAGGAGCUGGGUCCGUACCUGGUCUAGGAGCUAGGUCCGUACCUGGGCCAGGAGCUGGGUCCGUACCUGGGCCAGGAGCUGGGUCCGUACCUGGGCCAGGAGCUGGGUCUGUACCUGGACCAGGAGCUGGGUCGGGACCUGGUCUAGGAGGUGGGUUGGGACCUGGUGUAGGAGCUGGGCCAGGAGCUGGGUCUGUACCUGGGCCGGGAGCUGGAUCGGUACCUGGGCCGGGAGCUGGAUCGGUACCUGGGCCGGGAGCUGGAUCAGUACCUGGGGCAGGAGCUGGGUCUACACCUGAGCCAGAGCUAGGGCCUGGGCUCAGACAGGGGUCUGGGACUGGGCCCAGACCCAGUGAGUCAACAACAACCCCAACACCAGCGCCGCAGCAGAAGACUCAAGCCAAACCUACAAAGGCUGCCAGGCAGAAGGUUCUAGUGACUGGAGGAGGAGGCUACCUGGGCUUCAGCCUGGGAUCCCACCUAGCCAAGAGCGGCACUUCCGUCAUUCUGCUUGACCGCCGCAGACCCCAGUGGGAACUGUCCCCGGAAACCAAGUUCAUCCAGGCUGAUGUCCGAGAUGAAGAAGCCCUGUACCGUGCCUUCGAAGGGGUGGACUGUGUCUUCCACGUGGCUUCCUAUGGAAUGUCCGGGGCUGAGAAGCUGCAGAAAGAGCAGAUUGAGUCUAUAAAUGUUGGAGGCACCAAACUAGUGAUUGAUGUCUGUGUUCGCCGGCGGGUUCCAAGGCUCAUCUAUACCAGCACUGUCAAUGUUGCAUUUGGAGGGAAGCCCAUAGAGCAGGGCGAUGAGGACUCUGUGCCAUAUUUCCCAUUGGACGAGCACGUAGACCACUACUCCCGAACCAAAGCCAUCGCCGACCAAUUGACCCUCAUGGCCAAUGGGAUGCCUCUCCCAGGAGGAGGCACUCUUCGGACGUGUGUGCUCCGGCCUCCAGGGAUCUACGGCCCUGAAGAGCAGAGGCACCUGCCCCGUGUGGCGGGCCACAUCAAGAAGAGGCUGUUCAUGUUCCGAUUUGGGGACCACAAGGCACGGAUGAACUGGGUCCACGUACACAAUCUGGUGCAGGCACACGUGCUGGCGGCCGAGGCCCUCACCACGGCCAAGGGCUACGUGGCUAGUGGGCAGGCGUACUACAUCAACGAUGGGGAGAGCGUCAACCUCUUUGAGUGGAUGGCCCCACUGUUUGAGAAGCUGGGGUACAGCCAGCCCUGGAUCCAGGUGCCUACUUCCUGGGUUUACCUGACAGCAGCAGUUAUGGAGCGCCUCCAUCUGGCCCUGAGACCCAUCUGCAGCCUCCCACCGCUGCUCACUCGUAGUGAGGUGCGCAGCGUGGCCGUGACGCACACCUUCCAGAUAGCCAAGGCCCGCGCCCAGCUCGGCUACGCGCCGGAUAAGUUUAGGUUCGCCGACGCCGUGGAGCUAUACGUGCAGUCCACGACCCGGCGGCCCCGCGGCUCCACGGCGCGGACCCUCCUGCGCCUGCUGCUCAGGCUGCUGCUGUUCCUCGGCUUGCUCGCCCUGGCCCUGCACUUCCUAGGCCUGCAGCCUCUGCACGCCGCCGUGGAGCGCCUGUGACCGUCCGCCGUCCGCCGCCCGCUAGGGUCGGCCCCGCUGCACCCUCGCCCACGCCCGGCUCCCUGGGCUUGUACCAGCCCCUGCCCCGCCUUCUGGGUUUGAGCGCGCCUCCGCUCCGCCCCUUGAAUCCUGGUCACGCCCCCGAGCCGCUCUCCAGACCUAGCCCGGACCGCCGACUUCUGGCCACGCCCCUAUCUACUCCCAGACCUUGCCUUGCGCCCUUCCUGUGUUUUGGCCCCGCCCCUGUCCUGUCCCGCCCCGCCCUCCGAAGUGGGCACGCUCCUGCUCCGCCCCCUGAAUCCUGGCCACGUCCCUGGUCGGCCCAGACGCGUAGCCCCGAGUCUCUUUCCAUGUUUUGACCACGCCCUUGACCCGCCCUUCAAAUUGGGCACGCCUUCUUCCCCGCUCACUGAUUUCCUGGCCUAGCCCCUGAGCAGACCUCCAGACCUAGCCCCGCCCCCGUUUUAUAACCCCGCCCCUGCUUCACGGCUUGGGCACGCCUCUUCCCCGCCCCCUGACUUCAGAGCCUAGUCCUGAGCCGCUCUCCAGGCCUAACCCCGCCUUCAUGUCAUAGCCACGCCCCUUCCCGCCCUUCCAUGUUUGGGCACGCCUUCUGAGUCCUGGUCACGCCUCUGUCCCGCCCCCUGAAUCUUUCCUACGUCCAUGACCCUCCCUCCAGGCCCUGGCCCUGCCCCUUUUUUCCUCCCUCCGGCCUGUCCGGUUUCUGAUAUGGGCCAAGGCUCACAGCUUCCUCCGCCUUCUGGACCUUCUCCUAGUCCCUGCCCAGUCCCGGCCCACCCCCAGAUUCUCCCUCAUUCUGGUUUCGCCCCCUUUCUGGUCCUCCCCGCGCGCUUGAGCCCACCCUUUGGCUUCUCCUUUUGGGUCUGUCCUUGCUCCUGCCUCUGGACCCGGUCCCGCCCUUCUCGCGUGUAAUUGAGUCCUGGCCCCGCCCCCUCCCUCUCUGGCUUCACCCCUUUCCAGCUCCGCCUCCCGGGUAGGUUCUCCCCGGAACCAGGCUGCCGCGUCGCUAUGGGCUAACGCAGGCUCGGGUGACGUUGGUAUGAGUUUGCGCCGUCGGCUGCUGCUCUGUCUGGUAACAUUGCAUUCGAUCCACCCCGACCCAAUGUUCUGGGCUUCUCAUUCACACAGAUCUGUGUGUUGACAGCCAGGGUUUGGGGAAAAACCGAGACUCAAGCUUCUGCCGAGCCCGACUUGGCCUUUUUGGGUUCCUGUCUGAGGAUGACAGCAUAGUAAGCACAGGUUUUAGUACCAGAAAGAGCAUGAAAAAUUUAAAAAAAAAAACUCUUAAAAUAAUUGGAUGUCUCGAUGAAGUACCAAUAAAGCUAUAAUGGGAAAAA